AGCCUGCGUCUGCCAAUGAUCCAGGAGCCGCUCCUUUCCACUCGGGAAACCUUCAGAGGAGUCUCAGAAAGGACACGGCUGGCUGCUUUUCUCAGCGCCGAAGCCGCGCCAUGCUCGUCCUCAGAAGCGCCCUGACUCGGGCGCUGGCCUCACGGACGCUGGCGCCUCAGAUGUGCUCAUCUUUUGCUACGGGACCCAGACAAUACGAUGGAAUAUUCUAUGAAUUUCGUUCUUAUUACCUUAAGCCCUCAAAGAUGAAUGAGUUCCUGGAAAAUUUUGAGAAAAACGCUCAUCUUCGGACAGCUCACUCUGAAUUGGUUGGAUACUGGAGUGUAGAAUUUGGAGGCAGAAUGAAUACAGUGUUUCAUAUUUGGAAGUAUGAUAAUUUUGCUCAUCGAACUGAAGUUCGGAAAGCCUUGGCCAAAGAUAAGGAAUGGCAAGAACAAUUCCUCAUUCCAAAUUUGGCUCUCAUUGAUAAACAAGAGAGUGAGAUUACUUAUCUGGUACCAUGGUGCAAAUUAGAAAAACCUCCAAAAGAAGGAGUCUAUGAACUGGCCACUUUUCAGAUGAAACCUGGUGGGCCAGCUCUGUGGGGUGAUGCAUUUAAAAGGGCAGUUCAUGCUCAUGUCAAUCUAGGCUACACAAAACUAGUUGGAGUGUUCCACACAGAGUACGGAGCACUCAACAGAGUUCAUGUUCUUUGGUGGAAUGAGAGUGCAGAUAGUCGUGCAGCUGGGAGACAUAAGUCCCAUGAGGAUCCCAGAGUUGUGGCAGCUGUUCGGGAAAGUGUCAACUACCUAGUAUCUCAGCAGAAUAUGCUUCUGAUUCCUACAUCGUUUUCACCACUGAAAUAGUUUUCUACUGAAAUACAAAACAUUUCAUUAACUGCUAUAGGAUCUGUCUGCUAAUGGUGCUUAAAUUCUCCCAAGAGGUUCUCACUUUUAUUUGAAGGAGGUGUUAAGUUAAUUUGCUAUGUUUCUUGCAUUAUGAAGGCUACAUCUGUGCUUUGUAAGUACCACUUCAAAAAAUAGUUCUGUUUACUUUCUGCAUGGUAUUUCAGUGUCUGUCAUACAUUAAAAAUACUUGUCACUGUUUUAAGAUCUUGACUCUUCAUUUGUUUCAGAAUAGCUCUUCUACUGUAUUCUGACAACUCUUUGCUUUAUAGCAUUUUGUUGUAUUCAAAUGAUAAUGGUAGCAUUUCCAUGCUUGUGACAGCAUUUUUAAGUUAUUAAUAUAUUUUAUCAACCUUUCCAUCAUGUCUGUUUUCCUGGUUUUUUUUGGUUGUUUUUUGACCAGUAAAAUUUAUUUUGUAAUACCAAAUAGGAUUUAAGAAAAUUAACGUAUUUCUUUACUAUGGAAAACCACAUUGUCAUUUGUGACAUCAUCUAUAUUAAAUAUGGUUUUCACAUUAGUUAUUUGUCACUUACUUGGAAAAUGAUGCUGUUAGGUCCUGGUAUUAAAAAUCUAGAAAAGACUUGUUGGUUUAUGUGCUGAAAUGUCUUUAUUUAUAAUUAAUUUUAACUACUAUUUACUUCAUUUCGGAUCCUGUUUAACAAAGAUACUUGAGACAUCCAUUUGUUUUAAUGAAAUCUGUAUGGAUAUGGAAAUGCUUGCCCUAAUAAAAGCCUACAUAUAC